UGCACCACUGCAUUCCAGCCUGGGCAACAGAGCAAGACCCCAUCUCAAAAAAAGAAAAAAGAAAAAGAGGAAGGAUGGCUUACUGUACAAUGCCAUUUGUACUAAAAUAAUACCUGGAUAAUAUAAUGAGUGAUAUUAGUUAACUAGGCAGCUGCAUUCAUUAAUGAGCUUAAUUUCACCAUGAUGGUUUACAUUUCAGCUAGACAAGUUACUACUGAACUGGCUGGAGAAUGAUGGCAGAGGGUGAGAGUGAGAGUUGGUAUAGGAAGAAUUUGAAAAAUGAUUUUUAUUUUUUAUUUUUUGAGAUGGAGUCUUGCUUUGUCGCCCAGGCUGGAGUGCAAUGGCGCAAUCUUGGCUCACUGCAACCUCUGCCUCCCGGGUUCAAGCGAUUCUCCUGCCUCAGCCUCCCGAGUAGCUGGGAUUACAGGUGCACACCACCAUGCCCGGCUAAUUUUUGUAUUUUUUUAGUAGAGACGGGGUUUCACCAUGUUGGCCAGGAUGGUCUCGAUCUCCUGACCUGGUGAUCCGCCCACCUCGGCCUCCCAAAGUGCUGGGAUUACAGGCGUGAGCCACUGCACCCAGCCGAAAAAUGAUUUAAUAAGCAAUGUUAAGAAAUCAGAUUGGUUAAGAGGGAAGGGUUUAAUGAGGCCCCAAAGUAUCUAUUCCCAUGCACCCUAUGCCUGGAGAAAGCUGGGAUGUUCUACUCCAAGCUCUGUUGUCUUUUCUCUUUGGAAUAACUGGGGAGGUGUUUCUCUGGGUCUUCCUUCUGCCCCCAGGAUCCUGUGCUCUCUGGGUGUCCCAGCCCCCUGAGAUUCGUACCCUGGAAGGAUCCUCUGCCUUCCUGCCCUGCUCCUUCAAUGCCAGCCAAGGGAGACUGGCCAUUGGCUCCGUCACGUGGUUCCGAGAUGAGGUGGUUCCAGGGAAGGAGGUGAGGAAUGGAACCCCAGAGUUCAGGGGCCGCCUGGCCCCACUUGCUUCUUCCCGUUUCCUCCAUGACCACCAGGCUGAGCUGCACAUCCGGGACGUGCGAGGCCAUGACGCCAGCAUCUACGUGUGCAGAGUGGAGGUGCUGGGCCUUGGUGUCGGGACAGGGAAUGGGACUCGGCUGGUGGUGGAGAAAGAACAUCCUCAGCUAGGGGCUGGUACAGUCCUCCUCCUUCGGGCUGGAUUCUAUGCUGUCAGCUUUCUCUCUGUGGCCGUGGGCAGCACCGUCUAUUACCAGGGCAAAUAUGCCAAAUCUACUCUCUCCGGAUUCCCCCAACUCUGAACUUUCCCUUCCACCAGGUCUGACCUGGAAAGGUCCAAGAAGGCAGCUGCCGGCUGUGGUCCCAGCGCCCCUCCCACCACCAUGUGGGAGCUCAGCACAUCUGCUUCCCCCAGUCCCAGGAGGCUGAGCCUGAUUGUCCUGAGAAAUGGGAAGGAUCAGAUAUGACUCCUCCUUGGCAACUGCCCUUUCCUGCCAGGCCCACACAUACCCUCUUCUGGCUGUUAGGGGAGCUUGGGUCCCUGAACACUGUCAUUCACCCAAUAAAUUACUAUUUGACCCCAGAGUGGGUGGAAGGGUGA